GCUCCGCUCCGCACCACCAACCCCGGGCCGCAGUCCUGACGAGCGGGUCAGGGCUUGUCGGGCGGAAGCCUGGCCUGGAGCCUGGAAGGGGGAGACGGCCCGAGCGGGAGCGGGAGCGGACGCGGCCUCAGUCCUGCGCGGGUGAGCGUGCCCCGGAAGCUUGGGCCCCUGGCCGCCCUGGUGCCCCUUCUCCGGGACCUGGGGCGCUAGGCCGCGGCGGCAGAACUGGUGCCCCUGCGCGGCCUUCCUCCCAUCCUUACAGUUCCCCGUGUCCCAGGCCUCUACCCGGAACCGGAGCCCCGCCCGUCUCCUAGCAGCUCCGUGACGUGAAGCGCCUCGGGGUGCGGUGCCGCCGGGCGUGGGUGGGAGGCAACGCCCGAGGGGAGGGCCCGCCAGUGCACGGGGGUGCGGGGCGCGUUGGCGAGAAUUGGAGGCCGCGCCGCCGCCAGCCGUCCGCCGUCCCGCCCAGCAGGAGCACGUUCCCUUUCGCCAUUGGAAGACUGAGUUCCAAGCUUUUUCCUGCUCACCUAGAGCCGUCCCUGCCCCGCCCGCCACCCCCUGUACAUUUUCGGAGAUUUAGGAUAGUAAUUCUAGACCCUCGGUUGCAUUUCUGUUGGAAUUUUUCUGGAAGUUGGAAUCUGGCAGUUUAAACAAAGAAUUUUUUUAAGAAAAAUAUUUAUUAGUAUAUUUGAUAGUCCCCAGAUUAGGUUAAAAGCCUUAUUCCCAAUAACUGUAAUUUUGCAAAGACAUGUUUUUGGUGUAAAAAGGUAUAGAUAUGGGUUGAUGAAAAGAAUCAAACUCUGAAAAAUAUUUGAAGAGAUUUAUUUUGAGCCAGAUUCAAGUGACCAUGGCCAGUGACAGUCCUCAGGAGGUCCUGAGAACAUGUGCCCAAGGAAAUUGGGGUACAGCUUGGUUUUAUCUAUUUUAGGAAGGCGUGAGACAUCAAAUACAUUUAAGAAAUACAUUGGUUUAGUUUAGAAAGGCGGGGCAACUCAAUCGGUAAAUGUAAACGUUAUCUGGUUGAGGUUAUCUAAAGACCUGGGAUCCAUAAAAAGGAAUGUUCAGGCUAGAGAUAAAGGAUUGUGGAGACCAAGUUUUAUUGUGCAGAGGAAGCUCUUAGAUAGACUUUAGAGAGAGCAGGUUGUAAAUUGUUUUAUAUUGGACUUAAAAGGGUGCCUGGCUCUUAGUUGAUUAUCUCCUGGAUCUGGGAAGGAAGGAGGGAAAACAAGGGGAGAUGGGAAUUCUCACCAAAUGCAGAUUUUUCCUGCAAGAGACUUUGCAGGGGAGUUUUAAGAAGGAUUUACCCCAGAAUUUCUAUAAUAUCUGAUACUUCAAAGUGCAAAUAAUCAGUAAACGGAAAUAGACCAUGUGUACAAGGCUAUGUUGAGCAGUGUGCAGUGUUACAACACUGCUAUGUGUGAGGAAGAGGACUCCAUCUCUUCAUCAGUGGAAGCUGGCGAAUGGAAGAAAAGCUUGAUAUAAAGAGUGUCAUGAUGUCCUCACUAUUCCUUUCAGGCAUAACCCCAGGACACUCACUGUGUUGCCCAGGUUGGAGUGCAAUGAAUAUUGAAGGAUGUUUGUUCCAAGAUCUCUAAAAAUCAAGAGGAAUGCUAAUGAUGAUGGCAAAAGUUGUGUGGCUAAGAUAAUUAAACCAGACCCAGAAGACCUUCAGUUGGACAAAAGCAGAGAUGUUCCCGUUGAUGCUGUAGCUACAGAAGCAGCCACAAUAGACAGGCACAUCAGCGAAUCAUGCCCUUUCCCCAGCCCAGGUGGCCAGUUGGCAGAGGUUCAUUCAGUAAGUCCCGAGCAGGGUGCGAAGGACAGCCAUCCUUCUGAAGAGCCCGUUAAGUCAUUUUCCAAAACACAGCGCUGGGCAGAACCAGGGGAACCCAUCUGUGUUGUCUGUGGUCGUUAUGGAGAGUAUAUCUGUGAUAAGACAGAUGAAGAUGUGUGUAGUUUGGAGUGUAAAGCGAAACAUCUUCUACAAGUUAAGGAAAAGGAAGAGAAAUCAAAACUCAGCAAUCCACAGAAGGCUGAUUCUGAGCCAGAGUCUCCACUGAAUGCUUCCUAUGUCUACAAAGAGCACCCCUUUAUUUUGAACCUUCAGGAAGACCAGAUUGAAAAUCUUAAACAGCAGCUGGGAAUUUUAGUUCAAGGGCAAGAAGUCACCAGGCCCAUUAUUGACUUUGAACAUUGUAGUCUCCCUGAGGUCUUAAAUCACAACUUGAAGAAAUCAGGCUAUGAGGUGCCAACUCCCAUUCAAAUGCAGAUGAUUCCUGUGGGACUUCUGGGAAGAGACAUUCUGGCCAGUGCAGAUACUGGCUCAGGAAAAACAGCUGCUUUUCUUCUUCCUGUUAUCAUGCGAGCUUUAUUCGAGAGCAAAACUCCAUCUGCGCUCAUUCUUACACCAACCAGAGAGUUAGCCAUUCAGAUAGAGAGACAAGCUAAAGAAUUGAUGAGUGGCCUGCCACGCAUGAAAACUGUGCUUCUUGUAGGGGGCUUACCCUUACCCCCACAGCUUUAUCGUCUGCAACAACAUGUUAAGGUUAUCAUAGCAACCCCUGGGCGACUUCUGGAUAUAAUAAAGCAGAGCUCUGUAGAACUCUGUGGUGUAAAGAUUGUGGUAGUAGAUGAAGCUGAUACCAUGUUAAAGAUGGGUUUUCAACAACAAGUGCUUGACAUUUUGGAAAACAUUCCUAAUGAUUGUCAGACCAUUUUGGUUUCAGCCACAAUUCCAACUAGCAUAGAACAGCUAGCAAGCCAGCUUCUGCAUAAUCCUGUGAGAAUUAUCACUGGAGAAAAGAACCUACCUUGUGCCAAUGUACGUCAGAUUAUUUUGUGGGUAGAAGACCCAGCCAAAAAGAAAAAAUUAUUUGAAAUUUUAAAUGAUAAGAAACUCUUUAAGCCUCCAGUGUUAGUAUUUGUGGACUGCAAACUAGGAGCAGAUCUUUUGAGUGAAGCCGUUCAGAAAAUCACAGGGCUGAAAAGCAUAUCUAUACAUUCAGAGAAGUCGCAAAUAGAAAGGAAAAACAUAUUGAAGGGAUUACUUGAAGGAGACUAUGAAGUUGUAGUGAGCACAGGAGUCUUGGGACGAGGCCUAGACUUGAUCAGUGUCAGGCUGGUUGUCAAUUUUGAUAUGCCUUCAAGUAUGGAUGAGUAUGUCCAUCAGAUUGGAAGAGUAGGAAGAUUAGGUCAAAAUGGAACAGCGAUUACUUUCAUCAAUAAUAAUUCAAAAAGACUCUUCUGGGAUAUUGCAAAACGAGUAAAGCCCACAGGAUCCAUUCUUCCCCCUCAGUUAUUAAAUUCCCCAUACCUUCAUGACCAGAAGAGAAAGGAACAACAGAAAGAUAAACAGACACAGAAUGAUCUGGUUACAGGAGCUAAUCUUAUGGAUAUUAUCAGAAAACAUGAUAAAAGUAAUUCUCAGAAAUGAUUUUCUCUGCCACUUGAAUAUUUUUUUUUAUUGUAUAUAGUCAGCAAAAAAUUAUGGUUUGCAUAAAUGGAAAUGUACAUGAAUUUUAAAAAUUUUAAGAUAUUUUUAAUUUAAUAAAAUUUAUAUAACUAUAUUGUAUUUAUUUCCCUUAAUUCUUAUAAAUUAAAAACAUCAGAAAAUGAAUUAUUAAAUAAAAGACAGUGUUUUCUUUUCUGGA